ACUUCCCUAAGGUGGCUUUCAAAAGAGACACCAAGUGACAUAUUUUUAGGAGGGGUUUAAAAGUUUGAUGGGGUAGAAGUAAACGUUGCUUAACUCAACCAGCAGCAGAGCCAGGGCCCAGGGACCAGCGCUUCUGUGGACUUGGCCUUUCCAGCAGCAGACCCAGCAAUGAAUGAUCCGAACAGCUGUGUGGACAAUGCAACAGUUUGCUCUGGUGCAUCCUGUGUGGUACCUGAGAGCAAUUUCAAUAACAUCCUAAGUGUGGUCCUAAGUACGGUGCUGACCAUCCUGUUGGCCUUGGUGAUGUUCUCCAUGGGAUGCAACGUGGAAAUCAAGAAAUUUCUAGGGCACAUAAAGCGGCCGUGGGGCAUUUGUGUUGGCUUCCUCUGUCAGUUUGGAAUCAUGCCCCUCACAGGAUUCAUCCUGUCGGUGGCCUUUGACAUCCUCCCGCUCCAGGCCGUAGUGGUGCUCAUUAUAGGAUGCUGCCCUGGAGGAACUGCCUCCAAUAUCUUGGCCUAUUGGGUCGAUGGCGACAUGGACCUGAGCGUCAGCAUGACCACAUGCUCCACACUGCUUGCCCUCGGAAUGAUGCCGCUGUGCCUCCUUAUCUAUACCAAAAUGUGGGUCGACUCUGGGAGCAUCGUAAUUCCCUAUGAUAACAUAGGUACAUCUCUGGUUUCUCUCGUUGUUCCUGUUUCCAUUGGAAUGUUUGUUAAUCACAAAUGGCCCCAAAAAGCAAAGAUCAUACUUAAAAUUGGGUCCAUCGCGGGCGCCAUCCUCAUUGUGCUCAUAGCUGUGGUUGGAGGAAUAUUGUACCAAAGCGCCUGGAUCAUUGCUCCCAAACUGUGGAUUAUAGGAACAAUAUUUCCUGUGGCGGGUUACUCCCUGGGGUUUCUUCUGGCUAGAAUUGCUGGUCUACCCUGGUACAGGUGCCGAACGGUUGCUUUUGAAACGGGGAUGCAGAACACGCAGCUAUGUUCCACCAUCGUUCAGCUCUCCUUCACUCCUGAGGAGCUCAAUGUCGUAUUCACCUUCCCGCUCAUCUACAGCAUUUUCCAGCUCGCCUUUGCCGCAAUAUUCUUAGGAUUUUAUGUGGCAUACAAGAAAUGUCAUGGAAAAAACAAGGCAGAAAUUCCAGAGAGCAAAGAAAAUGGAACGGAGCCAGAGUCAUCGUUUUAUAAGGCAAAUGGAGGAUUUCAACCUGACGAAAAGUAGACAUCAAGUGGACAAAACAGACGAGUUCCAAAUUACGUUCUUAAACCGUAACUAUAUUUAAUUAUUUGUUUUGGUAGGACAGUUGGCAGAAAAGAGUUAAAGUGAAAAUUGGAAUUUCAUUGGAAUUCAUGUAUUGGUUUCAGUACCAAGUGACUGGUGGCCCAAUUCUUUAAUGGGACAAAUAUUGUUUCCUAUAUAUAUGUAUAUGUUUUAUAUAUGUAUGUAUACUCAUAUAGAUAUAUUGUCAUUGAAAUAUUCCCCCAAAAUAUUCUCAGACUAAACCUGACAUAGGGAACACCGAGAAUGAAAACAUCUUUAACACCAAAACUGAAUUCUUAUGCAGAAUUUCCUAGCCCAUAGAUGACAACCUGACUUUCUGUAUGUUAAAGUAGAUGUAAUGAAUUAUUAUUAUUACAGUGGUCACGAUUUUCUUCAGUGUUUAUGAUUAUAAAAAUUGACAUGAACAUCUUUCACUGACAUUUUAAUCAUUAUUUUAAAAGCUUUGCAACCUAUAUAUUUAUAUAACUUUGUAAUAUAACAUGGGCAAAUAUCUGACUUCUGUAUUUUUAAAAAGUUGCCUUCUCCAGUGGCAGUCCAAAAGCAGAAAUGAGAGGAAAUUAUUACAAAAUAGAAUUCAAUAACCAUAUUGGAUGCAGGCUCUUAACUCAGCAGGGAUAUCGUACAUCUAUUGCUCUACCUCAGGGGUCCAGUGAUACCCACUAGAUCUUCCAAGGAAAAACAUAAUUCUUUCAAACGGUGUGUAUUUGGCAAAGAGCUCUUCAAAUCUGGGAGAGGGACUUCCUCAAGGUUUUCCUGUGUGCAGUGGAUCCACAUAGCUAAUAUGACAGCUAGUCAGUUGACAGGGACCACCCACAGUAAGCACCAUGGUCAGGGAGGUGGCAGGAGGUGCAAAGACAGAAGUAUUGAGAGAAACACCAAGACUCUAGUGGAGGAAUUAAUUCAAUGGGAGAUAGUAUAAAAUACAUAGAAAACACAAGUAACAGAAACCUGGUUGAAAUGCUUAACUAGAGUCAAUUAGAUGUGCAGGAGUAAGUAGUAUAAGAAGAAUCAAGUCCGAGAGUGAUCAGGAAAUGAGUAUUAAACAGUAUUUGAAACAGAGAACGUGUCCCAGGGCCCAAAAGUCAGAAGGGCCCCACCAGCCAGGAAAGUUGUUUCAAUGCUGUAAGUAGGUGUAGCCAAGGGAAGCCAGGACUAUCUGAUAUACGGUAGCAGGGGUUUACGGCUGCCAGGGGAAAAUAACUCAUCAAGUGUUGGACUUUCAAUUAUAAGAUCGAAUUUAAUUUCCUUUCCCUCAUUCUGCAGCAAUCAGAAUACACAAUCUUAACCACUCGGUCCUUAGUGGUUUUGUUCCAUUUUGCAUUGGGUAUUUUCACUGCCUCAUAGAGUCUAUUUCAAGUGUUUUGGCUGAAAGGGCUUUUUGCAUUUGCAUGUUCUGAGUUCAGAUUCUGCUGGUGCACCCAAGCAUUAUGGGAACAGGAACUCAACUUAGCUCUUCCAGUAGAGGGGUGAGGGAUUCUGCUUUUCAAAUUCAUAACAUUGAUCUUUUUAUGCAAGAUUUCCAUUUACAGUUGAAUAAGUACUUCAUAUUUUUCCAUCAUUAGACAAAUACAAAAUGGACUAAAUAAUUUUAAGAGAUAGUGGAGGAGAGGGGGUACAGACUUCCUUCUUAGAGAGUGUCAGAGAAUAUGCUCCCAAUGGUGGAAAGGAAGAUUUACAGUCUAGCGGCUAAGUACCUCCUACACAUUUCCCAUCAAUCAGAAAAUAGACAGGUACACUAAAGGGACCCUGAGAACUCCUCUUGUAAUUUCAACACACCCAAAAUCAAGGGCCUGGAUGCCAGCAGCUGCAGCAAGCAGGUUUUUCCUCCCUGUUGAGCAAGACAGGUGAGCAAGAUAGGACUUGGCUUUCUUACAUGAUGCGGUAACUUGUGACUUGAGUCUUUUUCCCUAAUUUGCUAGUGGGAAGAAAAAUAGCUGAGCUUUCUAAAAUGAUAGCUCUCUAUUUUUAAAUGAAUUUGAAAAGUCGAUUAAAUUAUGUAUUUUAUUGCCUCUGAGUAUCAUAUUAAAUGAAUAUUUUAUUUUAAAGGCUUAAAUAAAUGAAAAUGAUUUUUGUAA